ACGUCAGAGGCAGGAACCGACUGUGCUAAGGCUGUUGGCUCAACACCCAGAGGAGACGGGCAGACCCAGGGAGAGUGAGAGAAGGGGGUCCUCUCUGACCCAAGGAAUUACCACUAGUGGAGUGAAGCCACCUGACUUUUUGAUCUUAUUUUGGUUGCCUCCUCAUUCUCCUUCCACCCGUAGCCCUGACAGCUUGGGUUUCAUUUCUUUCGUGGAGCCUUGUCUCUUCCUCCCAGAAUAGGAGGAAGGGAAGAGAAGGGAAAGAGGAGGGCUCUCUAGGUGAGCGCAUCAGCUGGCUCCAGCCUGAGCAAGCAAGAAUUUUCUUCCCAGGAAGCUCCUCUCGCUCCCCGGCCGCCCACCCCCAGCCUGGGUGGCUGUAUCGUUUUAACUGCAUAGAGGGCAGGUCUCUUUUGGAAUUAGGAUUAAAGAAAGUGCAGUAAAGAGAAAGCAUCGAAGACACCAUCACAAAAGAUUCCCACAACUCCAUGCUGUGUGCUGCAGGCUGGUCCUGAACCCAGAUCUCUGGCUGAGAGGAUGGGGGCAGAUGGGGAAACAGUGGUUCUGAAGAACAUGCUCAUUGGCAUCAACCUGAUCCUUCUGGGCUCCAUGAUCAAGCCUUCAGAGUGUCAGCUGGAGGUCACCACAGAAAGGGUCCAGAGACAGUCAGUGGAGGAGGAGGGAGGCAUUGCCAACUACAACACAUCCAGCAAAGAGCAGCCUGUGGUCUUCAACCACGUGUACAACAUUAACGUGCCCUUGGACAACCUCUGCUCCUCAGGGCUAGAGGCCUCUGCUGAGCAGGAGGUGAGUGCAGAAGACGAGACUCUGGCAGAGUACAUGGGCCAGACCUCAGACCACGAGAGCCAGGUCACCUUUACACACAGGAUCAACUUCCCCAAAAAGGCCUGUCCAUGUGCCAGUUCAGCCCAGGUGCUGCAGGAGCUGCUGAGCCGGAUCGAGAUGCUGGAGAGGGAGGUGUCGGUGCUGCGAGACCAGUGCAACGCCAACUGCUGCCAAGAAAGUGCUGCCACAGGACAACUGGACUAUAUCCCUCACUGCAGUGGCCACGGCAACUUUAGCUUUGAGUCCUGUGGCUGCAUCUGCAACGAAGGCUGGUUUGGCAAGAAUUGCUCGGAGCCCUACUGCCCGCUGGGUUGCUCCAGCCGGGGGGUGUGUGUGGAUGGCCAGUGCAUCUGUGACAGCGAGUACAGCGGGGAUGACUGUUCCGAACUCCGGUGCCCAACAGACUGCAGCUCCCGGGGGCUCUGCGUGGACGGGGAGUGUGUCUGUGAAGAGCCCUACACUGGCGAGGACUGCAGGGAACUGAGGUGCCCUGGGGACUGUUCGGGGAAGGGGAGAUGUGCCAACGGUACCUGUUUAUGCGAGGAGGGCUACGUUGGUGAGGACUGCGGCCAGCGGCAGUGUCUGAAUGCCUGCAGUGGGCGAGGACAAUGUGAGGAGGGGCUCUGCGUCUGUGAAGAGGGCUACCAGGGCCCUGACUGCUCAGCAGUUGCCCCUCCAGAGGACUUGCGAGUGGCUGGUAUCAGCGACAGGUCCAUUGAGCUGGAAUGGGACGGGCCGAUGGCAGUGACGGAAUAUGUGAUCUCUUACCAGCCGACGGCCCUGGGGGGCCUCCAGCUCCAGCAGCGGGUGCCUGGAGAUUGGAGUGGUGUCACCAUCACGGAGCUGGAGCCAGGUCUCACCUACAACAUCAGCGUCUACGCUGUCAUUAGCAACAUCCUCAGCCUUCCCAUCACUGCCAAGGUGGCCACCCAUCUCUCCACUCCUCAAGGGCUACAAUUUAAGACGAUCACAGAGACCACCGUGGAGGUGCAGUGGGAGCCCUUCUCAUUUUCCUUCGAUGGGUGGGAAAUCAGCUUCAUUCCAAAGAACAAUGAAGGGGGAGUGAUUGCUCAGGUCCCCAGCGAUGUUACGUCCUUUAACCAGACAGGACUAAAGCCUGGGGAGGAAUACAUUGUCAAUGUGGUGGCUCUGAAAGAACAGGCCCGCAGCCCCCCUACCUCGGCCAGCGUCUCCACAGUCAUUGACGGCCCCACGCAGAUCCUGGUUCGCGAUGUCUCGGACACUGUGGCUUUUGUGGAGUGGAUUCCCCCUCGAGCCAAAGUCGAUUUCAUUCUUUUGAAAUAUGGCCUGGUGGGCGGGGAAGGUGGGAGGACCACCUUCCGGCUGCAGCCUCCCCUGAGCCAAUACUCAGUGCAGGCCCUGCGGCCUGGCUCCCGAUACGAGGUGUCAGUCAGUGCCGUCCGAGGGACCAACGAGAGCGAUUCUGCCACCACUCAGUUCACAACAGAGAUCGAUGCCCCCAAGAACUUGCGAGUUGGUUCUCGCACAGCAACCAGCCUUGACCUCGAGUGGGAUAACAGUGAAGCCGAAGUUCAGGAGUACAAGGUUGUGUACAGCACCCUGGCGGGUGAGCAAUAUCAUGAGGUACUGGUCCCCAGGGGCAUUGGUCCAACCACCAGGGCCACCCUGACAGAUCUGGUACCUGGCACUGAGUAUGGAGUUGGAAUAUCUGCCGUCAUGAACUCACAGCAAAGCGUGCCAGCCACCAUGAAUGCCAGGACUGAACUUGACAGUCCCCGAGACCUCAUGGUGACAGCCUCCUCGGAGACCUCCAUCUCCCUCAUCUGGACCAAGGCCAGUGGCCCCAUUGACCACUACCGAAUUACCUUUACCCCAUCCUCUGGGAUUGCCUCAGAAGUCACCGUACCCAAGGACAGGACCUCAUACACACUAACAGAUCUAGAGCCUGGGGCAGAGUACAUCAUUUCCGUCACUGCUGAGAGGGGUCGGCAGCAGAGCUUGGAGUCCACUGUGGAUGCUUUCACAGGCUUCCGUCCCAUCUCUCAUCUGCACUUUUCUCAUGUGACCUCCUCCAGUGUGAACAUCACUUGGAGUGAUCCAUCUCCCCCAGCAGACAGACUCAUUCUUAACUACAGCCCCAGGGAUGAGGAGGAAGAGAUGAUGGAGGUCUCCCUGGAUGCCACCAAGAGGCAUGCUGUCCUGAUGGGCCUGCAACCAGCCACAGAGUAUAUUGUGAACCUUGUGGCUGUCCAUGGCACAGUGACCUCUGAGCCCAUUGUGGGCUCCAUCACCACAGGAAUUGAUCCCCCAAAAGACAUCACAAUUAGCAAUGUGACCAAGGACUCAGUGAUGGUCUCCUGGAGCCCUCCUGUUGCAUCUUUCGAUUACUACCGAGUAUCAUAUCGACCCACCCAAGUGGGACGACUAGACAGCUCAGUGGUGCCCAACACUGUGACAGAAUUCACCAUCACCAGACUGAACCCAGCUACCGAAUACGAAAUCAGCCUCAACAGCGUGCGGGGCAGGGAGGAAAGCGAGCGCAUCUGUACUCUUGUGCACACAGCCAUGGACAACCCUGUGGAUCUGAUUGCUACCAAUAUCACUCCAACAGAAGCCCUGCUGCAGUGGAAGGCACCAGUGGGUGAGGUGGAGAACUACGUCAUUGUUCUUACACACUUUGCAGUCGCUGGAGAGACCAUCCUUGUUGACGGAGUCAGUGAGGAAUUUCGGCUUGUUGACCUGCUUCCUAGCACCCACUAUACUGCCACCAUGUAUGCCACCAAUGGACCUCUCACCAGUGGCACCAUCAGCACCAACUUUUCUACUCUCCUGGACCCUCCGGCAAACCUGACAGCCAGUGAAGUCACCAGACAAAGUGCCCUGAUCUCCUGGCAGCCUCCCAGGGCAGAGAUUGAAAAUUAUGUCUUGACCUACAAAUCCACCGAUGGAAGCCGCAAGGAGCUGAUUGUGGAUGCAGAAGACACCUGGAUUCGACUGGAGGGCCUGUUGGAGAACACAGACUACACGGUGCUCCUGCAGGCAGCACAGGACACCACGUGGAGCAGCAUCACCUCCACCGCUUUCACCACAGGAGGCCGGGUGUUCCCUCAUCCCCAAGACUGUGCCCAGCAUUUGAUGAAUGGAGACACUUUGAGUGGGGUUUACCCCAUCUUCCUCAAUGGGGAGCUGAGCCAGAAAUUACAAGUGUACUGUGAUAUGACCACCGACGGGGGCGGCUGGAUUGUAUUCCAGAGGCGGCAGAAUGGCCAAACUGAUUUUUUCCGGAAAUGGGCUGAUUACCGUGUUGGCUUCGGGAACGUGGAGGAUGAGUUCUGGCUGGGGCUGGACAAUAUACACAGGAUCACAUCCCAGGGCCGCUAUGAGCUGCGCGUGGACAUGCGGGAUGGCCAAGAGGCCGCCUUCGCCUCCUACGACAGGUUCUCUGUCGAGGACAGCAGAAACCUGUACAAACUCCGCAUAGGAAGCUACAACGGCACUGCGGGGGACUCCCUCAGCUAUCAUCAAGGACGCCCUUUCUCCACAGAGGAUAGAGACAAUGAUGUUGCAGUGACUAACUGUGCCAUGUCGUACAAGGGAGCAUGGUGGUAUAAGAACUGCCACCGGACCAACCUCAAUGGGAAGUACGGGGAGUCCAGGCACAGUCAGGGCAUCAACUGGUACCAUUGGAAAGGCCAUGAGUUCUCCAUCCCCUUUGUGGAAAUGAAGAUGCGCCCCUACAACCACCGUCUCAUGGCAGGGAGAAAACGGCAGUCCUUACAGUUCUGAGCAGUGGGCGGCUGCAAGCCAACCAAUAUUUUCUGUCAUUUGUUUGUAUUUUAUAAUAUGAAACAAGGGGGGAGGGUAAUAGCAAUGUGUUUUGCAACAUAUUAAGAGUAUGUGAAGGAAGCAGGGAUGUCGCAGGAAUCCGCUGGCUAACAUCUGCUCUUGGUUUCUGCUGCCCUGGAGCCUGACCCUCAGUCUCCAUUCUCCCUCCUACCCAGGCCUCCUCAACCUUCACCUCCUUUCCCACCAAGGAGGAGAAGUAGGAAGUUUUCUUAAAGGGCCAAUUCAAAGCCAAGUCGUGGGGUGCAGAUUGUUAUGGUGACAGGCACACACAUUUUUCUACCCUUCUUCUGAGAUGUCCUCUGCCUUCCAGGUAUUUGUGAUUUUGUCACAGCCUGACAUGGCCAGGUUCUCACACUGGCCCAGAGAAAAGAGCCUCAGCAAGAGAGUUUUGCCAACAAUUCCCCUUAAAAGGAAACAGAUCAACUACACCGCAUCCCAACAACCCAGGUUCUUUUCCUUCCUUCCUUCCUUCCUCCCUUCCUUCUUUCCUGCCUUCCCUCCUUCCCUCCUUUCUUUCUUGACAGUAUCUCACUCUUGCUCAGUCUGGAGUGCAGUGGUGCAAUCUCAGCUCACUACAGCCUCGACUUCCUGAGCUUAAGUGAUCCUCUCGUCUCAGCCUCUUGAGUAGCUGGGACUACAGGCAUGAGCCACCAUACCUGGCUGAUUUUUCUUUUAUUUUUUGUAGAGAUGGGGGUCUCACUGUGUUGUCCAGGCUGGUCACAAACUCCUGGCCUUGAACAAUCCUCCCACCUCAGCCUCCCAAAAUGCUGGGAUUACAGGCUACAGCCACUGCAUCCAGCCCCAAGUCCUUUAUAAUGGGCCAAAGAUUCUCAUCUUCUGACACUCUUAUUAUACCAGCCACAUGUCCUGUUACCUUUCAAGAACAGUGGCUCUUUUCUGGCCCUGAUGGAGUCUUUUGCCUAAUCCCAUCCUGUCUUAGACCCCAGAGCCUCAAAAGCCCAACCAGCAUUUUGGAAUCUAGUUCCCAAGGCAUUGCCUGCUCCUGGCCCUGGGUGGCACAGUGGCUAUGUGCCUGUGAGUCAUCAGCCACUGCCCCCACCCUCAGGUCAGACAGACAGUCACUUUCUGCAAAGGUAGGAGGGGGAGAUGGUUGUAGUUUUUAGCACUUUUGGGUCAAGCAUUGAGGAAAGGACUGAAGAAGUCAAAAUCAGGGCACUGCCAUAGAGAUUAUAGUUUCCAUGGGAAACACAGAUCUUCCCUAGCCCUGUUUUCUCCAUUUCUGGUCCUAUUUGUCACAGAUUCUUUUUUUCUGAAUUGCAAACCGAAGGCCUCAUAUCUAUCUUCACCCAAGCCCUCCUUAGUGUAGGUGGCUUAAUAAGAGUCAGGAGAAGAAGGUAUAUGCCCAGAGAGCUAUACCCCUGACUGAUAAUCCUGGAAAGAGGUUGAUUUUUUUUUUCUUUUUUGGUCCUAUGGGAAACAGGAAUGACCUUCUUAAUGAGGUGAGAUCAUGAGAAGCCUUUCCAUCUUCUUUUAUUAUUCUGCCUUGCAAAGGAAAAAUGACAAUAGCCAAAGGAAAUUACAUCCAGAAAUCCAAAGGUGAAUAGGUGAUAACUGUGGGCCUACUUCCCAUUUUAUGAGAUGCACUGUCUUCACUAGCACAAUUUGAUCUUAAGCCCAAGAGAGCUAGAUGCUCUAGAAGCCGUGACCUUUCAAUUUCUCCUCCAAAUCCAAUAUCAGCAACCAUCCCCGCAACAUCUGCCCAGAUCCAUGCCCAGUUCCCUGAGCUGUCUUCUCCCUUUCCUCUCCCAUUCCUCAAGGCCCAGCACCAUUUUCUGUAGUGCCUAUGUUUGUCUGACCAGAGCAGUGUGUACCUUUGCCAACCAGUUACUGGAUGAGCCUUAGUGUCGGCAAUUUUCUAAUGGAAAUAUCCUCACUCUUACCAAGCUUUGAGAACCAAGAUGAAAAGUCCCUUGGGCUGACCAUCAGGCCUCGGACCUCAUGGGGAUGCAGCCAGCCACCAUUGAAUGGAGGCGCUUCCCUUGCCGCAGGCUUCUAGGCUUUGUUCACUGCGGCAGUGUGGAUGUGACAGGCAUAACCCUGAAAAACCUAGGCACCACUUGCAUUUCUCAGUUAACCAUGGGCUUCAACAAACUGGGAGGAGGAAAAAACAGAAACAGAUCCUUUCAACAAGCAUGUAAAUUACAGAAGACUUACCUAGAGACGGGGCAACAAUGAAUAGUAGGAAGCACAUUGCAUGGGAAACUUGAGGGCCGAGGUACAGGCCAACAGCUGUCAUCUUAGCUACGACAUGACAUCGGCUGGGUUGUUUCACCUCUCUGGGCCAGUUUCUUCAUCUGUCAGAUGAGAGAUUAGACUAGAAUGAGUUCUAAUUUCCCUUUCAGUUUUGACGGUCAAUGAUGCUAAUCUGUGAUCUGAAAACCUAAGUAGAAAUUGGCAUGGUGGGACAGCACAAUUAGGUAAUGAAAAUUCACUAGACUCCCUGUUUAAUGAGGAAAGAAGGAAAGAAGGAAGGAAGGAAGGAAGGAAAGAAGGAAGGGGAGGGAGGGAGGGAAAGAAAAGAGAGAGAUUGAUUCAGGAGUCAUAAGUAAAACACACACACACACACACACACACACACGAAAAUACUGCAGAAAAGAUCAUGCCGAGUGAGAGGCUGAACUCUUUUUGUCCAUAAAAACAGAGACCAGGUACCUGGGUGGUGCCAGCACGCCCACUUCAUCAAGGAAGUUGAAAUGGAAAAAGAUUAUGUGUUGUCAAUUCAGGUGAAAGUCAAGAAACAUCAGUGGAAACAAAAAUCUUCCUUUUAUUGAAACCAUUCUACACUAUGGAACAUUUUUAUAAAUAGUACCAGCGGCAUUGCAUAGCUUUAUUUUGAAGCAAGAAAGAGACUUCAAAGAUCAGCUUAUUCAACCCUCUAUAAAAGGAUUUAUAGAUUCCUUUUAUUUAAUAGGGUGAUUUUCUCAUGAGUUUUCACCAUGUUUAAAAGACACUGUGCCCCACUCUCAUCCCAAGGUCUAUGGUCAACUUGACUCAAUGCUCAUAACUUUCCUCGCUGAUUCCUGCUUAUCCUGCUCCUCCAAGCACAACUGCAUUUCCCAAAGGUAGAUCCAGUAAGCAAUACUCUCAAAGCACCCACCCUAUGCACACCAGUUUCCCUCAAGGGACUCAAAAGGAAUCGAGGUAGACCCUUCUCAGAGGCUGUUUAACUACAGACACAUCAGGAUAUGUACUAAUACCCAAAACCAAAACCACCACCAAUGACUGCAAUAGAUUCACUGUCUAGACCCAAGGUCCAGGCAGUUUCCCUUUUUUGCAUUUCCCCAACAUAUAAAGAUAAUUUCCAACAUAUCAGAUGCACAUUCACCAGGGUUAUUUCUGGAAGGUGAAGGGGUCAGGUGUAGAAGAGGUGGCAAGAAUGACAAGUCUGUGGAAAACUGUUGGCCUUGAGACCACAGUGAACUGGUGGAAGGGGACUUGCUAAGUGUGGCCACAAGGUGGCAGUCACCUCCUGAAACCCCGUGUGAAACGUCAGCGGGGUUGAGAAAGGCCACGUCUCCAAGUUUCCAGGAGAGCCAAACCAGGACUCAGGAAAACCGGCCAGCUGAUUUGUAUGGGAGAUUGAUUUGUAAAAGAACAACAACAACAUAUGGCAGCAAGGAAAUGCAAAGCAAACAUCUACAAAUAUUUGAAUCCACCUGUCCCUCACCUACCAACUUCCCCCUCUACUACUCAUAAAGUGGUAGGACUCCUAAUGCCCCGCUUCCUUCCACCUGAGAACCAACCAGCACCCUGAUAUUUCAAAGCCAGACCUAAAGAACCAUGGUUGCCAAUAACCUCAAUGCCAAACCAAACAAUCCUAAUCACAUUUUUACUUUUCAAAUCCAGUCUCAGAGCAGAGCUGUAGAUUAAGGGACAAAAAGUCAUUGUGGAAUCUUUUCAAAUAGCUCUUGUAAAAGCAUCAGUUGGGAAAGAGUUUAUGAGUUCCUCUUUGUCCUCUCCUCUGGAGAAAAGACAGAACAUGCAAGAACACUAGAUACACCAAGCUAUGGGUGUUGAAAUAGACUAGCUGGUGACCUGGAUUUGCAAAUACCCUAGGGACAUGAAAACAUUUUUUCUUUUUCUUUUUCUUUUUUGUAACCUCCACCCAGAAUUUCAGGAAAGGUGGGGCCACAUGCCCAGGAUAUAUGGUAUUCUACUGCUUGCUUUCUUAUCACCAGAAUACUAGUCAAUCUGAUUUCUUAGUUCCAUGUCUUUUCUUCCAAGGAGGUAGGGCAUGGGGUUGGGGGACACUUUCCGCCUUCCUUGCAUCUCACUGUCCACUCUUAAAUUUUUAUUAAGAAACCUCUGAAAGAUUCAAAAUUCAGUUCAGUUUCAAUAAUCCCAAAGAAGUUGGGAUAAUUUGUUUUCACUUGCUUCAAACUUGCCACGGCUGCAGGAGGAGUCUCAGGACCUCAGAGGAAUGGGGCAGAUGUGUGAAGUCUGGGAGUCUGCCUCCCACCCAGAUGCCAGGAGCUGCAUACUCAGCUCUGCCUCACUUCCCUGAUGGUCUGCUUUCAUCCAGGUUACCAUGACAGAGAGGGUCUAUCCUCUAAAGAAAGCUGAGUUACAGGCUGGCCCCUGGGGUUGUUCCUGUAGCCUCUCUUUGACCACAUUCCUGAAGAUGUUUAGCUGAAUGCCUCCUCAAACCUUUGCUUCUUCCAUAACCCAAUCCUACACAUAUGUGAUAAAGCUUUCUUCAACAAUACUGGGUCAUUUGGACACUACCAGUCCAGAUGAGAACUCACAGACCAAAUGAAAACUUUCAAAAGCAAGCAGGGAAAGUAACUCCUAUAUGCUUUAAGAUGAUGUAUUGGUGUAGAUUCAGGUCCAAUUUGAAAAAAUGUCUCUGGUUCUUUCUAAUUGUAUCCACUCUGGAUUUGUUUAUGCCAGUUCUACAUUCAUCAAGCCUUGAGAAACAGGUGGAAAGAAGAAAAAUAUAAAAUUAAGAAGAAGCUGAUGGAUCAUUGGAGAUUCAAAACAAGCCUUCUACCGGUGGCACCACACUGAAAGGCAGAGACAAGGCAGGAGCGGCCAUGGGAGAGGAAGCAGCAUUGGCUUCUCACGUUCUGGCCUCCAGCCUCCCACCAGAGCUUCUGCCAUUCACCCACUUAACUUGAGGAGAAACUAAGGCACCAAGGCCUGUCACUGCACCGAAAACCAGAAGCAGAAGGACUUUCUUUCUUUGCUCAACCAGUUCUGCCUGGAUCUGACUUUUGCGUCACCAGUAGUCACAAGCCUGAUUUGUCAUCUCCAGCAUUCUGUUUAUUUUUUUAAGGUCAAUCUUUGCCUGAAACAUGACUUCAUUGCACCUGCAGCACUUCAUUGUCCAAAUGUCCUUGGCAAACCUCACAGUCUUUGGACAGUGUUGCAUUUUCUCCAAAGGGGAAAUCCUCUCUCCUUCCUCAAGCUUAAUAAGGCUCUUGCAGUGCAUCCAAAUAACACAGCUCUUGUUCCUCAGACACACUCAGCCCCCUCUGAUAACUUCAUAAAACAGCUCCUUAUUGUCUGGGCCAUGAAGCCAGGCUAAUGCUAAAGUUCCAGUUCAAAAACAUUUAACUCUAUUAUCCUUAUGAGGCCAGCUCUCCUGGGUACUGGCACUCACUCACUGGCACCAUGGAUUCAGGUCAGGUGGUGCAAACAUCUUCCCUGAGAAGCAAGCCAUACACCCAACAGGUCUAGAACACCUAGGUCACAAGAAAGGGUUUCAGUCCAGAUGCACUGUCAGUAAGUGAACACAAGGACAAGAAUGCAUGAACUGUUAUUUUCUUCCCAUCACUGGUUUAGCAGCCCCUAGGGAGACCCUGUGUUGCUCUUUAAUAUUCUGACAUGGAGCACUAAUAUGCUCAACACUGCCUCCAACAGGCAAAUGUUGGAAAUACACUUUCAGAGCUGGAUGGGACUCAAGAUCAUCUAAUAUAAUCCUCUCAUUUUAUUUCCUCUCAAGGAAACCAAGGGCAAGAAAGUUUAGGCAAUUUGCUCACAUUCACACAGGCAAUUAGUAACAGAGCUGAGUUCGGGUCUGGUAUAGGCUUUUUAAUUUGAUUCUCCACAAAUGAACACUAAGAUAAAUAGCAUUUAUUGCAUACCCACUAUUUACCAGAUACUGUGCAAAGGGCUUUACAUAUAUUACUUUACUAAAUCCUCACCAUAAACUUUAAGUCAGGUUUAACCAUUUUAUAGAAGAGGGAAGGGAGGGCCAGGAAGGUUAAGUAACAUGCUCAAAGUCACACAGCUACUAAAUAGAGCCAUAAUCUGAACCUUUGUCUAAUUUUGAAGCCCUUGAUUUUUCCACUUCAUGAGGCUGCUCUUUAUAUUUAUUUAGCUGAGUGACCACCAUCUUGGAUUUUACUAAUAUUCUUACAAGGGGGCUUUGAUGCCACUUCUUCUGACUUUUAAGAAAAGGAAAUUCUUGCAUUAUUUUUGCCAUGUACUCCAGGGGACCCUCAAUCUCAUCAUCAUGGGGAAUAAGAAACAUUCUGACAUCUCUUUCCUUUUCUUUCUUUUUAAAUUUGGUAGACGAGGGAGAGGGUCCCCAACAGAAUGAGAGGGGGAAGAUAAGAACCAGAACAUAAACCCAAUACCCCCCACCCCACUCUUUUGGGAACAUCCCAACAUUAGAAGAGUGGGAUAUCCAGUCAUUUUUUUCAAGCUGGAGCAGGCAGUGUAGCCAGGAUUGAGGAAGGAGAAGCCACAGAAUAAACAUGGCACAUGUUCUCAGAGCAUCAAUUUUACUCCAGAAUUUGGGAAGAAAGGAUUAUAUUAUUAGUGUAUUCAAACCAGUAUGGAUAGCACAAAUGCAGAUAUCCUAUAAAUUUUGAGGCUAACUCCAGCAGGUUGUAGACUGAUUUAGGCUACCUCCUUCCAGACUCCCAGGGGUACAAACACCUUCACAGUCCCCUGCGGGAGUACAUCAGUGGAAAUAUUUGGGGAAUGAGGCUAGAAGGCAGGAGAUACAUUCAGUUUACUUAUCCCCCUGGUUUCUUUUCCCCACUCCUUACCUGCCCCACAUCCCUAGUGGGUGGGAAGGCAUCAGAAGACAGUUGGCUACAAUAUCAGCUUUCUCUGCUACUUUGGGGAAUUUAGAAGGAAAUCAGUACUUGGCAACCUGGUAUUUUUAGCUGCCAGGCCAAAACUCCAGACAUAAACCCCUUCCCUUUAAUUGAAUGAUGUUUAUAUAUAAAGGAAUAGAUCUCCCCAAGAAAGAACCCCAGAACACUGGUUCCAUUCCAGUGUGGGGGCUGCUUGGGCAGCAGUGACACCUGUGCAUUAGAUGCAAUAGACACUUCAAUUCCUGCAAAAAUGUCGGCCAACUAAGUGCUCCUUUACCAACUGCGGAGGCCCAGACUCACACCAUGGUCCCACAGACUCAAGGUUUAGAAUCUAUGUGAGUCUAUUUUGGUUAACACACAGGCUCCUCCUUCCAAUCAUUCACACACACACACACACACACACACACACACACAUGCACACACACACAUGCAUGCACACAUACACAGGUGCACAUGCACAAACACACACAUCUAAUGAUUCCAACCUCGAAUACUCCCCAGGCCCAUGGGGAUGCCCAAGUACCCUAAGCAAAUCACUGUGACACUGAGGGGGUCAUUAACUGGGGCUCCGAGCAGCUGAAACCCACCCUGGUGGUCUCUAGAUUGUUGUUCUGAGAAAUCAUAAACACCAAAUCCUCCAAUCCCUUUGAAUUUGAGUUUGUCAUUUUAACCUUUAACAGCCUUUUCAGGUAAAAAUAACAAAGACCAAUUUAUUGACUUUGUAGCUACAAUGAGCUUGAAAAAGCGCUUACUUAAAAGAAAGACUGGAAGGAAGAAAAAAAAAAGAAAAUGGAGUACAUACUCCUCAGACGAUGCACACUUUAAUUAGCUAAAAUAAAAAUAAAAAUGUACAGAGGAAGGGAGAGGAAAAACCAACUUCUCUGAUCCUUUCAUGGCACUGUAGCUCAAAGACUGGAAUCUCUGCUUGUUAACCAUUGUUAACUAGUAUUUUUAGUCCUGGUUGCUUUUAGCCUCUGUAUAGUUCCUUUUUUAAACACAUUUUCUAUACGUUAAUAAAAGAUCCUGAAAGAAA